AGUACCCAAGCGAGCCAUUUAACAUGGCGGAGGAUGUUUCCUCAGCGGCCCCGAGCCCGCGGGGCUGUGCGGAUGGUAGGGAUGCCGACCCUACUGAGGAGCAGAUGGCAGAAACAGAGAGAAACGACGAGGAGCAGUUCGAAUGCCAGGAACUGCUCGAGUGCCAGGUGCAGGUGGGGGCCCCCGAGGAGGAGGAGGAGGAGGAGGAGGACGCGGGCCUGGUGGCCGAGGCCGAGGCCGUGGCUGCCGGCUGGAUGCUCGAUUUCCUCUGCCUCUCUCUUUGCCGAGCUUUCCGCGACGGCCGCUCCGAGGACUUCCGCAGGACCCGCAACAGCGCAGAGGAUUAAAACCUUCAUGGGGGCAGAGACUGGCUAUCUGAAGUCAUCACCUCCUAACACAGGCUGGCAGUAGAUGUUCACUAUUAUUCAUGGACUAUCCAGUCUAACAGCUUGCCAGUUGAGAACGAUAUACAUAUGUCAGUUUUUGACAAGAAUUGCAGCAGGAAAAACCCUUGAUGCACAGUUUGAAAAUGAUGAACGAAUUACACCCUUGGAAUCAGCCCUGAUGAUUUGGGGUUCAAUUGAAAAGGAACAUGACAAACUUCAUGAAGAAAUACAGAAUUUAAUUAAAAUUCAGGCUAUAGCUGUUUGUAUGGAAAAUGGCAACUUUAAAGAAGCAGAAGAAGUCUUUGAAAGAAUAUUUGGUGAUCCAAAUUCUCAUAUGCCUUUCAAAAGCAAAUUGCUUAUGAUAAUCUCUCAGAAAGAUACAUUUCAUUCCUUUUUUCAACACUUCAGCUACAACCACAUGAUGGAGAAAAUUAAGAGUUAUGUGAAUUAUGUGCUAAGUGAAAAAUCAUCAACCUUUCUAAUGAAGGCAGCGGCAAAAGUAGUAGAAAGCAAAAGGACAAGAACAAUAACUUCUCAAGAUAAACCUAGUGGUAAUGAUGUUGAAAUGGAAACUGAAGCUAAUUUGGAUACAAGAAAAAGUGUUAGUGACAAACAGUCUGCGGUAACUGAAUCCUCAGAGGGUACAGUAUCCUUAUUGAGGUCUCACAAGAAUCUUUUCUUAUCUAAGUUGCAACAUGGAACCCAGCAACAAGACCUUAAUAAGAAAGAAAGAAGAGUAGGAACUCCUCAAAUUACAUAUAUUUGUCUUACCAAACUGACUAUGAAUAAGAAAGAAGGAGUGAGGAAAGGAUUAUGCUUCUUAGUACUCCUAAAACAUUAUCGUACAAAAAAGAAAAAAGAAAGCAGAAGAGCCACUGAAAGCAGAAUACCUGUUUCAAAGAGUCAGCCGGUAACUCCUGAAAAACAUCGAGCUAGAAAAAGACAGGCAUGGCUUUGGGAAGAAGACAAGAAUUUGAGAUCUGGCGUGAGGAAAUAUGGAGAGGGAAACUGGUCUAAAAUACUGUUGCAUUAUAAAUUCAACAACCGGACAAGUGUCAUGUUAAAAGACAGAUGGAGGACCAUGAAGAAACUAAAACUGAUUUCCUCAGACAGCGAAGACUGAUUGUGUUUGUAAAAGCUUGAUGAAAGGACAGUUAAGUAUUUUGAUCACUGCAUUUUGUUUGAAACUUGUGUCAUUGAUGUAAUUUAAAACUUUUGUUUAAAGCAUUACAGUAUUUUUCUGUGACCAUCAAUUAAUGAGGGUUUGUGCUACCAGAGUUAAAGCAUAUGCUAUCAUUGUAUUCUUUAAGAACCUUAUUUUGAUAAAAUGUAAAUUUGUUGAACCCUGCCACAUUUAGUAUCCCCACCCCCAAAUCCUGUUCCAAUGAAAAAAUUAAAACCUGAUACGAAAAAAAAAAAAUUCCAGUUAACCUAUUUUGUGUCUGUAGGCUGACCUCAACCCUGUAACGUAACCCAUUAAAAUGAAUUUCUUUUUUUUUAAGACAGAGUUUCUCUCUGUUGCCCAGGCUGGAGUGCAGUGGCGCAAUUUCAGCUCACUGCAACCUCUGCCUCCCAGGUUCAAGUGAUUCUCCUGCCUCAGCCUCCUGAGUAGCUGGGAUUACAGGCACACACCACCACGCCCAGCUAAUUUUUGUAUUUUUAGUAGAGGCGGGGUUUCACCAUGCUGGUCAGGAUGUUCUCCAACUCCUGACUUCAUGAUCCACCCACCUCGGCCUCCCAAAGUGCUGAGAUUACAGACGUGAGCCACUGCGUCCUGCCUAAAAUGAAUUUUCUAGAUGAUUGAAUAACAGUAGUCCUUUGAUAGAAGAUAAUGACUUGGUUUAUGGCCUUAAUAUACUACUUAAUUACUUAAGAUGUUUAUUAAUAGAAUGAUAAAUGUACAGAGUAACCUAUAAGCAUGACAUACUUUUGCUUUCAGUAGUUUCAUGUAAAGAAAAAAACUUGAAAAUAGUAAUACCUGAGUACCCAUGGGAAUAAUAGACACUGGGGAGGUAGGGUGGGGAGCGGGAGCAAGAGCUGAAAAACUUACCUACUGGGGACUGUGCUCACUACCUGGGUGACAGGAUCAUACGUACCCCAAACCUCAACAUCACACAGUAUACUCAGCUAACAAACCUGCCCAUGUGUUUCCUGAAUCUAAAAUAAAAAUCGAAAUAAUUUUUUUAAAAAAGAAAAAGACAAUAGUAUUACCCAUGGGACAAAAUUUGUACUAUUAGCAAGAAUCAUUUUGUGUCUCAUUUAGAAACAAUUUGACUUUUGUUCCAGUGUUUAAACUUUGACAAAAAUGGUUUUGAAUAGAUCUUUAUAACCUGAUGCCAUAAAUACAAGAUUCUCUGAUACCUUCAUUUAAUAUAUCAAUAUUGGGCCUAAAACAGUAUUCUGUAAAGCUUAAAUUGGUAUUAACUAUGAUCAUCUUGAUGUCUAUGAUAGAUAAUAAACAAGGUCAUACAUACCUUACUAAACAAUUUUGGUUUUUCACCAACAUUUUAUUCUUUAAAAGAUUUAGACUAACAGAAUUAUUUAGCAUUUCGAGUCAUGUGCUUUAUUUAGCAAGUGAGUAAAAAUAUUGGAAUAUUGAAGUAUUUGCAUAAAAAAUCAAAUGGUGGUGUUUUGUAAUCUCUAUUGUAUUUCCUAUUAAGGUUUCAUAUAUUACUUUCCCAUUGUUCCUGAAUUUGUUAUCCUAUAUAUAAACAGAAACAUGGAUGAGUACCAUAUACUUCCUGACUCCUUUAUCUUGUUACACCACAAGAUACUGCACUAUUUAUUGGAGAUAUUUUGAUGAUUAGUGCCAAGGCUGGCAUCAUGAGCCAAAAUAGACUUGUUAAGUCAACCUCAUUCCAAACACCUGCUAUAGAUCAUCAAAUCUAAGUUGCCAUUAAUUGUAAGAUGUCCUGUUAUUUCACACACACAACUAGAAAAGAAAAAUCGGUAUCAAUUAUAGUAUGGUGCUUUCUUAUUUUGAAUUUUACUUAUUAGAAGAGCUAUUUUAGAUGUAUUUAAACAUAAGAUUUUUAUCACAUAACUUGUGGAUACAAAAAAAGAGAAAUUGUAAGCAAAAUAAGUUGGGUAAUAUAUUCCUAAAACCUCA